GGGAUUUGGCGGUGGCCUUUGUUGGCUGCAGUAAGAGCUCAGUCUCUUCACCAGGGGCUCCCAGUCCUUCCAUCUGGGAGGCCAAGGCGGCUUCGCGUUCUGAGAAUAGACAGAACCUCUGUUACUCUGUGACCGGCAGGCACCGGGAGAUCCGUAGCUCAGACGCCAGGACAUCCCGGAAGCUGGGAAAUGUGGAGGAUUUGUGACAGUGGAUAUCUGUGUUCCAUAUUCUACUGCUAUCUGGAUGUCCGACUUUAAUGCCAAAUGUUAUGAGACAGGACUUGGCACCUCCUAGAAGUGUUCACAUAUACUAAAUGAUCUGCUAUUAUGGAAAUAAUUAAAUGACAUGUUUCUUGCUCGAAAGAGGUAUUUUGGCCUUACCUGUUGAAGUAUAAAGUAAGGAAAGGAAUGCAUCAUCCAGGAUUUGUUCCUCCACUCACAGAAGGAAUCUCUUUAUUUGGUAUCCAAAUGGGAUUUGCUCCAGUUUUCUAAUACGUGGACGAAGAACAAAGAGGAGUUCUGGAGACUCAUACUGAUAGGGACUGUUGACAUUCAGGGAUGUGGCCAUAGAAUUCUCUCGGGAGGAGUGGGAACACCUGGACUCAGAUCAGAAGCUUUUAUAUGGGGAUGUGAUGUUAGAGAACUACGGAAACCUGGUCUCUCUGGGUCUCGCUGUCUCUAAGCCGGACCUGAUCACCUUUUUGGAGCAAAGGAAAGAGCCCUGGAAUGUGAAGAGUGCAGAGACAGUAGCCAUCCAGCCAGAUAUCUUUUCUCAUGAUACUCAAGGCCUCUUAAGAAAGAAGCUUAUAGAAGCAUCAUUCCAAAAAGUGAUAUUGGAUGGAUAUGGGAGCUGUGGCCCUCAGAAUUUAAACUUAAGGAAAGAGUGGGAAAGUGAGGGUAAGUGUGAAGGUCACAAUGGAUAUUAUGAUGGACAUACAAAAUGUAAGACAACUACCUAUAACAAAAACCUCACUGUUACAGGAGGUCAAAAACAUGAAAAAACUCAAUUUAUGUCAGUUGCUUUUUCUAAACCAUGUGUUUCUGUAAGUAAGUGUCAACAUCAAUUUUUGAAACUUACCUUUUCUUUUAAAGGAAAUUUGGAUAAUCCGAAUAGUGACUUAGUCCAUGUUUCAAAUAAUCAUUUAAACCAAUUAAAAUAUAGAACUGGAGUAAAUGUUCAGUCAAAUAUUUCUGAAAAGGAGAGAUUUAAAAACGAGGAGGUGAUUUCUAAAUAUGAUCAAUUUGAUGGAUCUUUGUUAAAAGUUUGUUUCACCAACAAAUAACACCUCGUUCUGCCUGUGAUCAAUAUAGAAAGGUCUUCAUUCAUUCAUCAUUGCUUAAUCAAUGUCAAGGAAUAGAUAAUUUGGGAAAAUAUCACACACAUAAUAAAACUUUGACAGCCUUUAGGCAGGACUAUACCCUAAAUAAUUACCAGUAUAUUUGUGUUGCAGAGAAAAAUCAGUACAAUAAAUCUGAUACAACAUUAAGCCAAGGCAUAAGCCCCAGAAGACAUCAGAAAACUCAUUUUCUACAUAACCAUUGCAAACGUAAAAAAUGUGAGAAAGCCUUUCAUGAAUGCACCAACCAUGUCCAUCAGAGUAUCUUUAUUCAAGAGAAGUCUGCCAAAUGUAAUAAGUGUAUAGAAACUUUUAUCCAGUCAUCAAAACAUACUCAGCCUCAGAGAAUCCAUAUUGGAGAAAAGUCACACAGAUGUAAUAAUGGUGAGAAAAUCCUUAGUAAAUUGUCAAGUCUAAGAAAACAUAAGAUAAUCCAUAAUGAAGAGAAACCUUACAAAUGUAAAGAAUGUGACAAAGCCUUUAACCAUCGUUCACACCUUACUCAACAUCAAAUAAUUCAUACUGGAGAGAAACCAUACAAAUGUAAAGAAUGUGGCAAAGCCUUCAAUUCUAGUUCAUAUUUUACUAGACAUCAGAGAAUUCACACUGGAGAAAAACUUUACAAAUGUAAAGCGUGUAGCAAAUGUUUUACUCAUUCUUCAAAUCUUCUUGUGCAUCAGAGAAUUCAUACUGGAGAGAAACCUUACAAAUGUAAAGAAUGUGGUAAAUCAUUUAAAGUGUCUUCAGCCCUUACUCAGCAUGAGAGAAUUCAUACUGGAGAGAAACCCUAUAAAUGUAAGGAAUGCAGCAAAGCCUUUAACUGUAGGUCGUACCUAACUAAACAUCAGAGAAUUCAUACCGGAGAAAAACUUUACAAAUGUAAAUCAUGUAGCAAAUCUUUUUCUCGUUCCUCAAGUCUUAUUGUCCACCAGAGAAUUCAUACUGGAGAAAAACCCUAUAAAUGCAAAGAAUGUGGCAAAGCCUUUAAUUGUAGUUCACGCCUUACUCAACAUCAAAGAAUUCAUACCGGAGAGAAACCCUACAUAUGUAAAGAAUGUGGCAAAGCCUUUAACUGUAGUUCAUCCCUUACUAAACAUCAGAGAAUUCAUACUGGAGUAAAACUUUACAAAUGUAAAGCAUGUAGCAAAUCUUUCUCUCAUUCCUCAUGUCUUUCUGUGCAUCAGAUAACUCAUACUGGAAUGAAACCAUAUAUAUGUAAGGAUUGUGGCAUCUCCUUUAACCGGUCUUCAAACCUUAGACGACAUCAGAUGAUUCAUACUGGAGAGAAACCCUACAAAUGUAAAGAAUGUGGCAAAUUAUUUAAUCGAUGCUCAACCCUUACUCGACAUAAAAGUAUUCAUACUAGAGAAUUUCUAUAGUUGUAGUAAAUGUGAAAAGAGUUUUAUCCAAAAUUUAGAACUUAAAAAUCACCAUAGAGUUUAUAGGGAAACCGACUUUACAGAUUGAAUAAAUGGGAGGAAGUAUUUAAUCAGAACUCAAAUCUGAAUGUGUCAGGACUUACACAAAAAAGGACUAAAGCACAGAUCCCCACUUUAAAAUUAAAUAAGAGUAUUUGUUAUGGAGGAUUACUCUAAAGCCAAAGCAGUUACUUAUUUUGUUAUGUGUUUCAAAUGAGCAAAAGCAUUGAUGUUUGGACAAGUAAUUAUUCAGUGAGCAUGUUAUUUGUAUUGAAAACAUUUGAAAUUUGUAUAAAGCAAAUCAUAAUUUAAUUCUCAGAUUAGUUGUUAUACCUUAAUGCCUAGUGUUUAUAUAAAAACAUAUAGUCUAUUUUUUCUGCAUCAGAGCUGUAAGAGGUCGUUCUAUAGUAGGUGAACAUCAUUAAUAUCAACUUAUUUUCUUGGAAAUUUAAUGGCAAAUGUAAAAUACAUGAAGAAAAUCUAAAAGAGGCUCUUUGUGUUUGAAUCAUUAAACAGUAAUAUGUGUAAACAUAUAGUACAUAUUUAGGGCAUUAGUAUUCUAUACUAAAGUAAAAGAGGAAUAUUCUGAAUUUAUUUAUUACAUCAAUUGCUCCUUAAGUAGAAAAACACUGGUCAGUUAUUUAAAAUACUGGCAUACCUUUAUAGUACAAUGAAGUAGUAAUCUUGAAUAUUAUUUGAUGUGUUAAAAAUAAAAACAUCUUCACAGAUAUCAGAGAAAAGUGAAAACUCAUAUCUGAAAGAUUAUAAAUAUACUUUAUAUCAAUUUUCCAGAGAACUUAAACUUCUAAUAAUAUUGGUAAUAUUCUCAUGGUUACUAUUUUAUAUUCUUUCCUGCUUUUUGUAGCUACUGGUGUACUAUGACAGUUAUAAUAAAGAUUAUAUGGGGGUAUACUUAAAUGCCAUACUUUUAAAAUCCUGAAUCAUUGUUUAUAAAGUUUUAUUCAAUAUUUUUCUUUGCACAUGCCCUUUUUCAGUCCAAUUGAACACUUAGAGAUUUUUCUUUGCUUUCACUUGCAUUAAAUGGAAUAUACAGAUGUACUAAGAUAGAAAGAAAAAGGUGAAAGAGAACUAUACAGGCAGAAAUGCAUGUGUGUGUACCUGUCUUCAAAUGGAAAAGAAAAUGAUGGAUCACAACAGGAAACUGGAGAACUGUUGAUUUAUUACAGUUCUCAAAUUAGAAACCUCCCAAAUUCUUAAAGCUAAAUUAGCUUUUCAUUGCACACUGAAUUUUUCUCUGAUAAAUCUAAUGUCUUCUGGGUUCAGACUUUAUCCCGUACAAAUCCUUUUUUCUUGCCUGUGAUUCAUGUGAGAAGAAUUAUAUAAUUUUCUUAUUUCAAAGCUUAUAAACUAUUACUUAUAAGUUCUCAUGGAUUUUAAGAAUGUUUUUGUAAAAUUUAAUGGUGCUGUCCAGGUGUGGUGGCUCACGCCGGUAAUCCCAGCAUUUCGGGAGGCUGAGGCAGGAGGAUCAUUUGAGGUCAGGAGUUUGAGACCAGCCUGGCCAACAUGGUGAUAUCUCGUCUCUACUGAAAAUACAAAAAUUAGCUGGAUGUGGUGGCACACACCUGUAAUCCCAGUUACUCAGGAGGCAAAGGCAGGAGAGUUGCUUGAACUGAGGAGAUGAAGGUUACAGUGAGCCAAGUUUGUGCCUCACACUCCAGCCUGGGUAACAGAGUGAGACUCUGUCUAUAAACAAACAAAUUAUCUGUCAUCUACCUAUAGACAUAACCCUACUGAGGAGGAUGGGGAUAAAAGGUCUGCAUCUAAGUCACUUUGAAAAACAGUAUUUUGAUUGAAUGCUGUAAGACUACACAAAUGCUGUAUUCUACUGAGUAAUAUUUUAUUUUCCUACAAGGAUAUGCAUUAGCAAUUCUGAAACAGUUUUACAUGUUAUUAUAUAAUAUAUGGAGGCUGUUUCUCAGUGUAGUUCACAAAAGUUAAAUGGUGAAUGCUAGCAUGAAUCUUGUGGUCCUAGCCCAAAGUUGGAAAUAUCAGGAUGAACCCAUGACUAAUACAUCUGGAUGGAUGGAUGGAUGAAUAGAUAUAAAGAUAGGUAGGUAGGUAGGUAGGUAGGUAGAUAGAUAGAUAGAUAGAUAGAUAGAUAGAUAGAUAGAUAGAUGAAGCGAUGUCUAAGAUAUCUGGAAGGAUGGAUGGAUGGAUGGAUGGAUAGUUAGAUAGAUAGAUAGAUAGAUAGAUACAUAGAUAGACGAUUCAGAGAUAGAUAAUGUUCCAAACUCUUGAGGGCCAAGAACUGGUGACAUCUUGUAUCAACACAUCUAGGUCUACAAUCUUGGUUUCUAAACAACAUUCAUUAAAAGGACCCAAGGGUUGAAGUUAGAAAAUACAAGUUGAGCUAGAGUAUCUUGUAAAGCCACAAAGAAAAAAGUGCUUAAUAAAAAUGAUGGGGACUUUUCAAAGGGAGCCAACCUGAAAGACCUCCCAAUGGUCCAAGCUCCAACAAUAUGAGCAAUAAGUUAUGAUAGCUUUGGAUUAUGGCCCACAGAAUAAAGUAAUACUCAUCUCUACUGUGUGAAUAAAAGAGAUUAAAUAAGGAAAGAAGGAAUGAAAUCUACAAUAUUUAAAAUACAGAUCAAUGUAGUUGGAUAAUGCAAAAUAAAUCAACACUAGAACAUCACAGUAAUAAUUACCAUAGGGAAGAUUCCCCGAGGAAUUCAAAAAUUUCAGGAAAAACUUAAACACUAAAGAGUGUAUUUGGGCCAGUCUCGGUGGCACAUGCCUGUAAUCCUAGCACUUUGGGAGGCCUCUGCGGGUGGAUCACCUGAGGUCAGGAGUUCAAGACCAGCCUAGCCAACAUGGUGAAACCCCGUCUCUAUUAAAAAUGAAAAAAUUAGUCGGGCAUGGUGGUGGGUACCUAUAAUCCCAGCUACUUGGGAGGCUGAAGCAGGAGAGUCACUUGAACCUGGGAAGCAGAAGUUGUUUUGAGCCAAGAUCAUGCCAUUGCACUCCAGCCUGGGCGACAAGAGCAGAACUCUGUCUCAAAAAAAAAAAAAGAAAAGAAAAGUGUAUUUGCAUAUUUUAAGUAUCUACCAUCUAAUAUUUAUUAAUACAAUUUUUUCUUAAUUUCUUAGACUUGUGACUAUUUGAAACAAAUUAUAACACUGUAUUGUAGGAUUUAUAAUUUGUAGUUGUAAAAUUUAUAACACAUGGAAUAAGAAGAUAAAUGGAACUGUUCUGUAGCAAAUUUUUCAUGUUUUAUAUUUAAGACAGUAUAGUAUUAACUCUAAAAGUAUGGUGGAUAUGUUAAAGAUUCAUAUUGUAUUCCCUGCAGCAACCACUAAAAAAUGCAAAGAAGUGUAAUGUAAAUGCUAAAAAAGGAGAUAAUUAUAAAAUAUUUAUUUGCACAAUAUUUAUGUAUCUUUUAGUCAUAAUAGCCCAAAACAGGAAACAACCAAAAUGUCCAUUAAUAAGAAAAUGAACUAAUUGUAUAGCUUUUAGAACAAAAUACAGCUCAGGAAUAUGAAAAACCAAGCACACAUCCUGGAUAAAAUUCAUAAACCUGCUCAAUGAGAGAAAAGUUGGACACAAAAUUGUACUUUAUGUAUUUUGUAUUUUAUUCCAGGCAAAAUAAUCCUAUGGUGAAAAAAAUCAACAAGAUAAUCUCUGCUUGAGAAAAAGGACCAAAGACAAGUGAAUUUUCUGAGGGUGAUGAAAGUGUUGCUUCGAAAAGGGGUGAAGUUUAUAUGGGUCUAUUUAUUUGUCUAACAUGUACAGUUAAGGUUUAUGCCUUGCAAUGUAUGUACAUCUUCACAAAAAAAAUCUUAAAAAAAUUAAAUGGGUGGGGGUAGGGAAAGGGUUGAAGUAUAGAUGAAGCAGAAGUGGUACAUGAUUAGUAGUUGAAGCUGGGGGCAGGUCUAUAUAUUUUAUUUUUAUGUCUUUAAUAGCAUUUGUAUAAAUGUACAAUAUUCGUUUACAAUGUUAGCUCAGGAUCUUGUUUACCUUUGGACAGGGAGGGAGGGAGAAAUUUAUUUUCUGGGUAGGAGUAAAGCUGGUUCUAUUCCUCAGUUAUGUAAAUUAUCUGUUAUAAUCCAAAAAGCUUUACAUGAAUGUUUCUGUAUGUAAUGUGGUAUAUCAAUAAAAAAUUAAAUAUUA